CUCUCAGUUGAAGCGCGCACAUUGAGUCGGCUUUUCUACUGCUUCGGCUAGGGUACCUUGUGACCAUGUCUUCCAAGAAGAAUAGAAAGCGGUUGAACCAAAGCGCGGAAAAUGGUUCGUCCUUGCCCUCUGCUGCUUCCUCUUGUGCGGAGGCACGGGCUCCUUCUGCUGGAUCAGACUUCGCGGCAACCUCCGGGACUCUGACGGUGACCAACUUAUUAGAAAAGGUAGAUGACAAAAUUCCUAAAACAUUCCAGAAUUCCCUUAUUCAUCUUGGACUCAACACUAUGAAGUCUGCAAAUAUAUGUAUAGGUCGACCAGUGUUGCUUACUAGUUUGAACGGAAAGCAAGAGGUGUAUACAGCCUGGCCUAUGGCAGGAUUUCCUGGAGGCAAGGUCGGCCUGAGUGAAAUGGCACAGAAAAAUGUGGGUGUGAGGCCUGGUGAUGCCAUCCAGGUCCAGCCUCUUGUGGGUGCUGUGCUACAGGCUGAGGAAAUGGAUGUGGCACUGAGUGACAAAGAUAUGGAAAUUAAUGAAGAAGAACUGACUGGUUGUAUCCUGAGAAAACUAGAUGGCAAGAUUGUUUUACCAGGCAACUUUCUGUAUUGUACAUUCUAUGGACGACCGUACAAGCUGCAAGUAUUGCGAGUGAAAGGGGCAGAUGGCAUGAUAUUGGGAGGGCCUCAGAGUGACUCUGACACUGAUGCCCAAAGAAUGGCCUUUGAACAGUCCAGCAUGGAAACCAGUAGCCUGGAGUUAUCCUUACAGCUAAGCCAGUUAGAUCUGGAGGAUACCCAGAUCCCAACAUCAAGAAGUACUCCUUAUAAACCAAUUGAUGACAGAAUUACAAAUAAAGCCAGUGAUGUUUUGCUGGAUGUUACACAGAGCCCUGGAGAUGGCAGUGGACUUAUGCUAGAGGAAGUCACAGGUCUUAAAUGUAAUUUUGAAUCUGCCAGAGAAGGAAAUGAGCAACUUACUGAAGAAGAGAGACUGCUAAAGUUCAGCAUAGGAGCAAAGUGCAAUACUGAUACUUUUUAUUUUAUUUCUUCAACAACAAGAGUCAAUUUUACAGAGAUUGAUAAAAAUUCAAAAGAGCAAGACAACCAAUUCAAAGUAACUUAUGACAUGAUAGGAGGAUUAAGUAGCCAGCUGAAAGCAAUUAGAGAAAUAAUUGAAUUGCCCCUCAAACAGCCUGAGCUUUUCAAGAGUUAUGGAAUUCCUGCCCCUAGAGGAGUGUUACUUUAUGGUCCUCCAGGUACUGGAAAAACAAUGAUCGCCAGGGCUGUUGCUAAUGAAGUUGGAGCCUAUGUUUCUGUAAUUAAUGGUCCUGAAAUUAUAAGCAAAUUCUAUGGUGAGACUGAAGCAAAGUUACGUCAGAUAUUUGCUGAAGCCACUCUACGACACCCAUCAAUUAUUUUUAUUGAUGAGCUGGAUGCACUUUGUCCGAAAAGAGAGGGGGCCCAGAAUGAAGUGGAAAAAAGAGUUGUGGCUUCACUCUUAACACUGAUGGAUGGCAUUGGUUCAGAAGUAAGUGAAGGACAAGUGUUGGUUCUUGGGGCCACAAAUCGCCCUCAUGCCUUGGAUGCUGCUCUCCGAAGACCUGGGCGAUUUGAUAAAGAGAUUGAGAUUGGAGUUCCCAAUGCUCAGGACCGGCUAGAUAUUCUCCAGAAACUGCUUCGAAGGGUACCCCAUUUGCUCACUGAGGCUGAGCUGCUGCAGCUGGCAAAUAGUGCUCAUGGAUACGUUGGAGCAGACUUGAAAGUCUUGUGUAAUGAAGCAGCUGGGACCAGAAUCCUAAAGGCGCAUAUGUAUGUCUCUGCCUUUGCCACGGGCCUCACCCAAACCCCUCAAGGUCUCUGUGCCUUGCGGAGAAUCCUGAAAAAACAGCCUAACCUCCCUGAUGUCAAGGUGGCUGGACUGGUGAAGAUUACUCUGAAGGAUUUCUUGCAGGCAAUGAAUGAUAUCAGACCCAGUGCCAUGAGGGAAAUAGCAAUUGAUGUCCCAAAUGUAUCCUGGUCAGAUAUAGGAGGACUGGAAAGUAUCAAACUGAAGUUGGAACAGGCUGUGGAAUGGCCCUUAAAACAUCCAGAGUCUUUCAUUCGAAUGGGUAUUCAGCCACCUAAAGGAGUUCUUCUCUAUGGGCCACCUGGGUGCUCUAAAACAAUGAUAGCAAAGGCUUUGGCCAAUGAGAGUGGACUGAAUUUUCUAGCUAUAAAGGGGCCUGAAUUAAUGAAUAAAUAUGUUGGUGAAUCUGAAAGAGCAGUUAGAGAGACCUUCCGAAAAGCAAGAGCAGUGGCGCCUUCCAUUAUUUUCUUUGAUGAACUGGAUGCCUUAGCAGUUGAAAGGGGCAGUUCUUUAGGUGCUGGGAAUGUAGCCGAUCGUGUUUUGGCUCAGCUCUUAACAGAAAUGGAUGGGAUUGAACAGCUAAAGGAUGUGACCAUUUUGGCAGCUACUAACCGUCCAGAUAGGAUAGACAAGGUAGAACUCCCUGUGGAACAUGAAUUUUUUUUAACUAUACUUUUGUUACUACUCAGAUGAUAUAUACUGUAUCAAAAGUGUAUGUCCUUGUCAAGUUCUCUAAAGUUUGUGAAAUACAAGAGAAUAUGCAGUAAAAUUUUAAGUCUGUUUCCUUUCCAGAUACUUUUUCUCUGAAGAACUACUGUGGAACAUUACUUAUAUUGUUUAAUAGUACUAUAAAGUUGUUUCCACACUUGUAUGAUUAGCACGUAAUGUUCAAACUGUGCCAUGAAUGUGCUGGUAGAAACAAAACAGUUUUAAGGACAAUUAAAACAACAACAUCCUGUUAUGAAGUAAAGACACAGUUUUUACCAUCUUUAUUGUCUGGAAGAAACUGUAGUAGGAAUAAAAGAGGCGACGAAGAGUUAAAGUACAUUUUAUGUUUUUAGGCUAAAACUGAUUAAAAAAAAAGAUCAUUGUAGGGUCAAAGAAAUUGAUAUAUAUAGUGUAAUUUUGGCUACAUUAAAUCCAGGCAUUUGGCCUUUUAAAUUAGCUAGCAUAUUUUACAAUCUUGUUGCCUCUUACCCCACAACCUCUAUGUUAUGAUGAUUUUAGGUUAGUAUGUUAAAACAAGGAGAAUUCCUGGACUGUCACAGGAGUGAAAUUGAUAUCAUUAUGUUACCCAUGUGUUGUGCAUAUUUAGUGUCUCUUUUUGACAGUAUUUCAGUUUCAUGUCUUCUGGGGAGACUAAAGCCAAAGUUUCUUGGGGAUUCUGGUGUUUUAGCAAAGACAGUGAGACACAUAGCUCAAGAACUGCGUUAUUUUACUCCUUGCUAUGUCACAUUUACAUGUCAGACUCAUUUGCUGUGAUGUAGCACACUAGGCUGGUGAAAUAAUUGCUUGUGAUGUCCCUAAGUCCCCGAGGCUUUUUUCUACCUCCUGCUUAGAUAGUGAAGAGAAGUUGAAGUUGAGUCCUCUAGUGUUCAUUUUGCGUAAGAGUGAUAGGAUGCGGUAGGACAGAUGAAGAUUAAUGAGAUUGUGUGAUAUCAAGUAGGCUCAUUGUCUUUAGAUUGAUUGCUGAUGGUCUGGAUUUGCUUAGCAUCAGGAGAGUUUAGAAACAAACAACUAAUUUAUUAAUGAUGCCCAAAUAAUAGUUAAAUGCCCAAACUUUUGGAAUUUAUGUUGUUCAUUGUUAACAACUGCUGUGUGGCCCCUUUAGAAGUGUCCAGUCCAUGACAUUUUAUACAUUUGUGUUGAAUCUUAAGGAAAACAUGAUCAUGUCUUCUUUCUCGGGUGAUAAGCAUGCCUCAAAAUAGUUUUAAUUCUGUGAAUAUCUUUGAAUUCAGUUUAUUUGGGUACUUUUAGUACGGAUACCUACUAUAUAACAAGCUCCUAAUAAGAACUAUUAAAUUAUAAGCAUUAUCCCUAGCGUAUAAACCUAGUUUUCUUGUAGUAGGAAAUUUGAAGGACUUCAAAAAUUUUACUUUAAGCCAUCUAUGGAAAAGAUUGCCCAAUUGAGAAAAAUUGUGAAAGAUAUGUAGAAGUCUUAAAUAAUUUUGGUUUCAGGAUUAUUUUCUAUUGUUGUGUUAGACUCAUGGAGGUAGUAAAUUGGCAUUAAUUUUCCUUACAGUUUUUCUGGAAGAGGAAAUGUGCUUAAUGAGCUAAAUAAGACAUAACAUUUUGUUUUCUUACAUUGUUGCAAAUUGAAGUUGGGUUUUGUUGUUUGUUUGUUUUGAGAUGCAGGUCUGGCUGUUUUGCCAGGCUGAAGUGCAGUGUCUAUUCACAGAUCAUUAAGUUGUGCAGCCUUAAACCUUUGGACUCAAGCAAUCUCCUGCCUCAGCCUCCCAAGUAGCUAAGAUUAUAGGUGUGCACCACAGCAUCCAGCUUAAAAUUUAGUUUUCUAGAAAGUUUUAUGACAUGGGGAAAAGUUAAUUAACAAUAUUUAGGAAUGUCCACAAAUAAAAAGCUAAAUAUACGUAUCUUUCGAUAUUCAAAUGACUAGUAUUCCAAAAAUACCCUCAGAAGAAAGGCUACAAAUGUUUCUUCAUUCUCCAUUUUUCCUAGUUAUAACUAUUGCUCUUCUAAUAUUACUCUUCUUAGCUAAGUCAGAACUAAAAAAAAAAAGCUGCAAGGACUAAUUGACAUUAAUAGUUCAAAUGAAUCAUAAUUCUUUACUUUCCCAAAAGUAUUUAAGGAAUGGAUGCCUAUUAAUCUUUCACAUUGUUUAUCAAAAUGAUGUGAAUAGUCUUUGGUGAGCCAUAUUAAGAUUAAAGCUGGAAAGCGUCCUGUACGGUUGUUUUCCAAUUUCAGCUUUGCCAUCUUUACACAAGACUCUCAUAAGUGUUUUUGUUAUUGUUGCUGGAUUCUUCUUUUGUUUGUUUUUAAAACUCCAGGUGUUUUAACUUCUAUGACAGUUAUUAUUCUUAUCUUCUAUGGCAGCCCCUUCCAAGUUUUGGCUUUGGGGAUAGAGAAUUGGGAGAGAUCAGAGAAGAGAGACUGGUGAGAGGUUGUAUGCAUAUGUGGGUCUUACUUCAUUUCGAUGUUCAUAAGAUAAAGACGCUUUAUCUCAAGGGUUGGCAGACCAUGGCCUUUAGGCCAAACGUGACCCACCAACUGGUUUUGCAUAUCCCAUUGUCUAAGAAUAGUGUUUACAUAUUUAAAUGAUUAGGAAAAUACUUUAAAAGUGGUUUUUUGUGACAUAUGAAAAUUAUAUGAAAUUCAGCUUUCAGUCCUCAUAAAUAAAGCUUUAUUAGAACACAUCCACACUAAUUUGAUUAUGUUUUGUCUGUUACUCCUUUUGCACUACUGUAGUAGAGUAGUUACAGUACAGACUUAUGGCCUAUAAAGCCUAAAUUAUAUACUCUAGACCUUUGCAGAAAAAGUUUCCUGACUCUUGAUUUGUCCUUGUAAGUUUUUAGAAGAUUAGUAGCCUUUAAUGUCUGUUGUUCAUAUAUGAACCUCACGUUUUUGUUUCUUUUUAAAAAAGAUUAUUUUAAUUGACAUAAAAAUUGUAUCUGUUUAUAGAGUACAACAUGUUGUUUUGAUAAUUGUGUAUUCAUUGUGGAAUGGCUAGAUCAAGCUAUUUAACAUGUGCAUUACUUCACAUACUUCUUAUUUUUUUGUGAUGAGGACACUUAAAACCAACUCUCUUAGUAAUUUUUAAGUAUACAAUAUAUUGUUAACGAUAGUCACCCUACAGUACAAUAGACCUCUUGAACUUAUUUCUCCUGUUUAACUGAAGGUUUGUAUCCUUUGACCAAUAUCUUCCCAACUCCCUUAGACCUCCAGGCCCUGAUAACCACCAUUCUACUUUCUGCUUUUGUGAGUUCAACUUUUUAAGACUCCACAUAUAAGCAAGAUCAUGCACUAUUUGCCUUUCUUUGUCUGGCUUAUUUCACUUAGCAUAAUGUCCUCCAGGUUGAUCCAUAUUGUCACAAAUGACAGGAUUUCCUUUUAAUAAAGGUUGAAUAGGAUUACCUUCUGUAUACAUACCACAUUUUCUUUAUCCGCUUAUUCUUCGAUGCAUACUUAGGUUGAUUCCAUGACUUGGAUAUUGUGAAUAAUGCUGCAGUGAACAUGGAGUGCAGAUGUCUCUUGGACAUACUGAUUUCAUUUCCUUUGGAUAUAUACUCAAUAGUGGAAUUGCUGGAUCAUAAGAUAGUUUUAUUUUAAAUUUUUUAGGAACUUCCACACUAUUUUCUCUAAUAUCUGAAGUAAUUUAUGUUCCUACCAACAGUGUACAAGGGGUCUCUUUUCUCCACAUCCUCACCAACAUUUAUCUUUCAUGUUUUUGACAAUAGCUAUUCUAACAGGUAUGAAAUGGUAUCUCAUUGUGGUUUUCAUUGGCAUUUCUCUGAUGAUUAGUGAUGUUGAGCACUUAAAAAAUAUACCUGUUGGCUAUUUGUAUGUCUUCUGAGAAAUGUCUAUUCAGGUCUUUUGCCCAUUUUUUAAUCAGGUCAUUUGUUGCUGUUGAGUUCCUUAUAAAUUUUGGUAUUUUAGAUUUUAACACCUUAUCAGGUUUGGUUUACAAACAUAUUCUCUCAUUUUAUAGGUUGUCUCUUCACUAUGUUGAAUGUUUCCUUUGCUGUGCAGAGGCUUUUUAGCUUCAUGUAAUCCCAUUAGUCUAUUUUUUCUUUUGUUGUCUGUGCUUUUGAGGUCAUGUUCAAAAAAUUAUUGUCCAGGCCAGUGUCAUGGAACAUUUUCCCUAUAACUUCUUUCAGUAGUUUUUCAGUUUUAGCUCUUUAUUCGUCUUUAAUUCAUUUUGAGUUGAAUGAGCCACAGAGUUUUUUUUUUUAAAGAUUGUUUAAAAUGUUUAACACGUACGUUUUCUGAAGAUACAUUAUAAGUCGUAUUUGAGUAAAAAAUAUAAUACUGAACUUAAAUAAUAGUAGGGAGGCUGAAUUAACUUAUUUCAAGCAUACACCAUCCCCUCUUGAAAGCUCUCUUAAUCUUUAAUUUUUUAAAAUACAUUUUCUUCCACUAAAUACUUAUUUUUUCCAACUGACUCCCGAAAACUCAUAAAUCUACAAUUGUUAUUACAUGAGUAAUGUAAAUAUUUAUUCAUGCCACCUGAAUCUUAAAGUUCCAUUGGUUAUUAGCUUUUUGUAGUUAUGAGUUGUAUGCCCUUUUUAGUAUUUAGCAACAUUGGGAUUUUCAGGCUUAGAUUUCUAAAUUUUGAAAGAUUCUGUGUUUAGAUAUAUUUGUUUAGUAAAUAAUAUUUGAUGUUGUCAACGUGAAUUGAAGUAUGUUUAAUAUUAGAGAAAGUAAUACCAUAAUAAAAUACAUGUUGCUGUCAAUACCCAAGGUCUAAAAGAAAUUUGGUUUUUCAAGACUGGAGAGGACAUAGAAGGCUCCAUGGUCUAGAUGACCCAUCUGAUACACUGACACCUGUUGUAAAAUCCCAACCCAUCAUUUCUUCAUCCUUUGCUUAUUCACCCACACUGAUGGGGAACUAUUAAUUCACGAAAUAGACCAUUUCAUUUUUGUGUCAGACUAUUAAGAAGUUCUUUAAUCCGAUGAACAAGCAGCUGUUUGUCUCCCUAAACCCUCUAUACCUCUACCUGAUUUUAUUCCAAAGUCUGUAAAGAACAGUUUUUAAUCCUUCUUCUAUAUGGUGUUCCUUUAUUUUUUAAAACUGUUAGUUAUCUUGUCUUUACACUUUAUCUCACUAACCAGUCUUUUGUUUUUCAGGCUUGACAUUUUGGAUUAUUUCAUAUGCCAUUGUUUUUCCGUCUAAAGCAUUCUCAUCUUUUUCUUGUGAACUAUUUGUCCUUUUUGCUCUGAAGUUGUAACAUCCACCAACAAAUAUAUAUUGAUUGGUUGUGUUCUAUCAGUACACAACUUAGUGAGACUCCUGCUGCCUCUACCCUGAAUACCUUGCUUCUCCUAAUGCAUUCCAGGAUUUUGUUAGCUUUGUUGUCAGCUGCACAUUGAGAUUGCUAUUGAAUAAAGUCAUCAGGAACAACAACAAAGGUGAAAAGCCCAGGUCUUUCUUCAAAGUCUGCUAAAUAAUAGUUUUCACGCCUUGGGCUUGUGCAGUUAAUUUGAUUUAAGUUUCAGCAACUGAGGCACAAUAUAUACCAGAUAUAGAAGUUAUCCUCCAAAAUUAGCUCCUCUAAGUUUCUCCUACUUUUCACAUGAUUCCCAGAUAUUCUUUUCUUUAAGUCCAAGUGAUUUCCCAAUUAUUUCCAUGGCUAUGGCUACAAAGGCUUUAGGCCAUAGGAAUAGAGGAAUUUAUUCUUACUAAAUUCAUCUUAUUAGAUUUGAUUAAUCUUCCCAACUUGUCAACUGUGGGAUCUUGUUUCUGUCAUUCUCUAUGUAUUUCUUUAUUCAUUGAUAGCAAAGGCACUAUAUAUCUUAAAUACCAAGAAGAAUUUAUAUAGCUUUCUUUUUGAAAAAUUGUUUAAAGUAUCUAGUUCAAGAUCCCCAAUCUAGGUGAACUUCAUGGAACAUUUAAUUGACAUGGAGAUAAUUAGGGGAUGUUCUGAAGAGUUACCAAAGAGAACUCCUAAAGAGAAACUAGAUGGUUGAGAUUAUUUAUGGAGGAAGAACAGAUGAAAGUAAAAUUCUGCUAUUAAGAAUACUAUCUGGGUAAAGAAAUGCUUUCUGCUUUCUUUGGUGGAAAUAGAUAAGAGUGAGCAGACUUAUAUUCAUUCAUUGAAAUUCAGAUAAAUUCAUAACCAAAGUUUUAUUAUAUAUAUACUGAUAAGGUGAAGAGUUCAACACUAAUCUAGUUUGAACUCCAUAGAUAUUUAAAACCAGCUAUUUUAAUUUCUUUUAGCUUUAAGACAAUGCUGAAAUAUGUACUUAAUUUUCUGAAUACUUUGCUCUUUAUAGUUGCCGUUUCAUGAAUUUGUGAUAUUAGACUUAUUGUAUGAGGAGUUUUGUAUUUUUCUUCUUUGAACUUUUUGCUUAUAGUGCUUUGGGCACAGACCUUCCCAAACCUUAGUAUUUCUGGAUGAAUUUUUUGAGAGUGCACAACAUUGGAAAGGAGCUUUUGCAUAAUGCCAGCAAUGUAGCUGAGGAAAUGGGUCUGGAGGAAAAUGAGAUUUGACACCUGUAACAGAGGAUAAAUAUGAUAGGGGCCAGAGUGCCUUAUACAGAGUGUGAUAGGAAAGCUCAAAACUAACAGAAACAAGCAAUGGAAGAGUAAAGGCAGACAGAUGGUUGCAGAGAUCUUAGUUUCUGAUGCUAGCUGUGUUAUUAACAGACUGUGUAUUAUUUGAAAUAAUUUAUCCUCACUGAGCAUCUGUUUCUGUACCUGUGAAAAAUGUACUAGAUAAUCUUUGAUAUAUCAUUCAAGCUCUACAAUUAUCUUCUUUUGUGACACAGAGACAGACAAGAAUAGAGAUUAUCAAUGUUAUAUAAAAGGAUGUUACUUACCAAACAAGUUUCUGAGGUUUUUGUUUUUUGUUUUCUGUUUUGUUUCUUUUUAGGUACCACCUUCCCAGACUUUCUUGUUACUGUAACGUUUAUUUCUUCAAACAGAUCAUAAAGCAAGCAGAUAUUAUCCAGGUGUGCAAAAGUGAUUAACCAUGUGAUUUUCAGAAAAAAAAAAAAAAAAAGAAAAAGCAAUCAAUCAGCCUUUAAGGCUGUUGUUGUGUAAUAAAAACCUUGCUUGACAGUUGAAGUACACCUUAACUUUUUCAUUUAAAAUUUAUUACUCUUUGAAAAAGGAGAACUUGUUGAGCAGCAUAUUUUCUUUUUUCACAGAUGUCUGAUUAGCCUGCAAUAUUUUGGUUCUAUUUAAUAUACUUUUAACUAUUUUUUAAUGAAUAUGAAUGUAAAAAUAAUGUUGAGUUAGAAUAGAAAUAUCUAACUGUAUGAUUAAAGUUGAAUCACUUAUAAAUUUGAAAAA